ACCAAGCCUUCCACGUGCGCCUUAUAGCCUCUCAACUUCUUGCUUGGGAUCUCCAACCUCACCGCGGCUCGAAAUGGACCCCAACUGCUCCUGCGCCACUGGUGGCUCCUGCACCUGCACUGGCUCCUGCAAAUGCAAAGAGUGCAAAUGCACCUCCUGCAAGAAGAGCUGCUGCUCCUGCUGCCCCAUGAGCUGUGCCAAGUGUGCCCAGGGCUGCAUCUGCAAAGGGGCAUCAGAGAAGUGCAGCUGCUGUGCCUGAUGUCCGGACAGCCCUGCUCGAAGAUAUAGAAAGAGUGACCUGCACAAACUUGGAAUUUUUUUUCCAUACAACCCUGACCCAUUUACUGUAUUUUUUUUAAUGAAAUAUGUGAAUGAUAAUAAAAGUUGCUGACUUAA